GGGCGGUUGCUUGUUGGUUGUUGUAGUAACCGGGGAAGCAGCCGUCGGCGGCUGCCCUGAGCCUUCCUGGGGAAGGAGGAGGGAGGUAGGCGCAGAGCGCGGUCCACGCCUGCUCGCCCCGAACCAUGGGAAGAUGAGACAGGAAUCUGUGCCAUCCAAAUUGCUUGAUCCAGUGAAUCUGCUAGGAAAGGUCUCUGAGGCCCCCGUCUGCUGACUGCAUGACAAACCCUAAAGGAAAUGCCAAUCGUGAUGGCCCGGGACCUGGAGGAAACAGCAUCAUCCUCAGAGGAUGAGGAGGUCAUAAGUCAAGAGGAUCAUCCAUGCAUCAUGUGGACUGGAGGCUGCAGGAGAAUUCCAGUUUUGGUAUUCCAUGCCGACGCUAUUCUUACAAAGGACAACAAUAUUAGAGUAAUUGGAGAACGUUAUCAUUUGUCUUAUAAGAUUGUACGAACGGACAGUCGCCUAGUACGCAGCAUUCUGACAGCCCAUGGAUUUCAUGAAGUUCACCCAAGCAGCACUGACUAUAACCUAAUGUGGACAGGAUCCCACCUGAAGCCCUUCUUACUGCGCACCCUCUCUGAAGCACAAAAAGUUAAUCACUUUCCCAGGUCUUAUGAACUUACCCGGAAGGACCGACUGUACAAAAACAUUAUUCGAAUGCAGCAUACACAUGGAUUCAAGGCUUUUCACAUCCUCCCCCAGACCUUCCUCCUGCCAGCUGAGUACGCGGAAUUUUGUAAUUCAUAUUCGAAGGACCGGGGACCUUGGAUAGUAAAACCAGUGGCAUCUUCAAGGGGGCGGGGCGUCUACCUGAUCAACAAUCCAAACCAGAUCUCCCUGGAAGAGAACAUUUUGGUCUCCCGUUACAUUAACAACCCCCUGCUCAUAGAUGAUUUCAAGUUUGACGUGCGCCUCUAUGUGCUCGUGACUUCCUAUGAUCCUCUUGUCAUCUAUCUCUAUGAAGAAGGAUUGGCUAGGUUUGCAACUGUGCGAUAUGAUCAAGGAGCCAAGAACAUUCGGAACCAGUUCAUGCAUCUGACAAACUACAGUGUCAACAAGAAAAGUGGAGAUUACGUCAGUUGUGACGAUCCAGAAGUGGAGGAUUAUGGAAACAAAUGGAGCAUGAGUGCUAUGCUUAGGUACCUGAAACAAGAAGGCAGAGAUACAACCGCAUUGAUGGCCCAUGUAGAAGACCUGAUCAUUAAGACUAUAAUCUCUGCUGAACUAGCUAUUGCUACUGCCUGUAAAACCUUUGUUCCUCAUCGCAGCAGUUGUUUUGAACUCUAUGGCUUUGACGUGCUCAUAGAUUCUACUCUGAAGCCAUGGUUGUUGGAAGUGAAUCUCUCUCCUUCUUUGGCCUGUGAUGCGCCUCUGGACCUAAAGAUUAAAGCCAGUAUGAUUUCAGAUAUGUUCACUGUUGUAGGAUUUGUGUGCCAAGAUCCUGCCCAGCGGGCAUCAACUCGGCCAAUUUAUCCCACCUUUGAGUCUUCCAGGCGAAACCCUUUCCAGAAACCUCAGCGUUGCCGUCCACUCUCUGCCAGUGAUGCGGAAAUGAAAAACCUCGUGGGCUCAGCCCGGGAGAAAGGGCCAGGGAAGUUGGGUGGUUCUGUGCUUGGUCUGUCAAUGGAGGAGAUCAAAGUUUUACGAAGGGUGAAGGAGGAGAAUGAUCGGCGAGGUGGAUUUAUUCGCAUAUUUCCUACAUCUGAGACAUGGGAAAUAUAUGGGUCCUACCUCGAGCAUAAGACCUCAAUGAACUAUAUGCUGGCAACACGCCUCUUCCAGGACAGAAUGACUGCUGAUGGAGCGCCAGAAUUGAAGAUAGAGAGUCUGAAUUCAAAGGCCAAGCUGCAUGCUGCACUUUACGAGAGGAAGCUCCUGUCUCUGGAGGUGCGAAAACGUAGACGACGGAGUAGCAGAUUGAGGGCAAUGAGGCCAAAAUACCCAGUGAUUACCCAACCAGCUGAAAUGAAUGUUAAAACUGAGACAGAGAGUGAAGAGGAGGAAGAAGUCGCAUUAGAUAAUGAAGAUGAAGAACAGGAGGCUUCCCAGGAGGAGUCUGCAGGAUUUCUUAGAGAAAAUCAAGCCAAAUAUACACCCUCAUUGACAGCUUUGGUAGAAAAUACACCCAAAGAAAAUUCCAUGAAAGUUCGUGAAUGGAAUAAUAAAGGUGGACACUGCUGCAAACUUGAGACUCAGGAGCUAGAGCCUAAAUUUAACCUGAUGCAGAUUCUUCAAGAUAAUGGCAAUCUUAGCAAAAUGCAGGCCCGAAUAGCAUUCUCUGCCUAUCUCCAGCAUGUUCAAAUUCGCCUGAUGAAAGACAGUGGCGGUCAGACGUUCAGUGCCAGUUGGGCUGCCAAAGAGGAUGAACAGAUGGAGCUGGUUGUUCGUUUCCUCAAGCGAGCAUCAAAUAACCUCCAGCAUUCACUGAGGAUGGUAUUACCCAGUCGACGAUUGGCACUUCUGGAACGCAGAAGAAUCCUGGCCCACCAGCUGGGUGACUUUAUCAUUGUAUACAACAAGGAAACAGAACAAAUGGCUGAAAAGAAAUCAAAGAAGAAAGUUGAGGAAGAAGAGGAAGAUGGGGUGAAUAUGGAAAACUUUCAGGAGUUCAUCAGACAAGCAAGUGAGGCUGAACUGGAGGAGGUGUUGACUUUUUAUACCCAAAAGAACAAGUCUGCUAGUGUCUUCCUGGGGACUCACUCUAAAAUUUCUAAGAACAACAACAAUUAUUCUGAUAGUGGGGCAAAAGGUGAUCACCCUGAGACUAUAAUGGAAGAAGUGAAAAUAAAGCCACCUAAACAGCAACAGACGACAGAAAUUCAUUCUGAUAAAUUAUCUCGAUUUACCACUUCAGCAGAAAAAGAGGCAAAAUUAGUUUAUAGCAAUUCCUCCUCUGGUCCUACUGCUACUCUGCAGAAAAUUCCCAACACCCAUUUGUCAUCUGUUACAACCUCUGACCUCUCUCCAGGGCCUUGCCACCAUUCUUCUUUAUCUCAAAUUCCUUCAGCUAUCCCCAGCAUGCCUCACCAGCCAACAAUUUUACUGAACACAGUCUCUGCCAGUGCUUCUCCCUGCCUACAUCCCGGGGCACAGAACAUCCCAAGCCCUACUGGCCUGCCACGCUGUCGAUCAGGAAGUCACACCAUUGGUCCCUUUUCUUCCUUCCAAAGUGCUGCACACAUCUAUAGCCAGAAACUGUCUCGUCCCUCUUCAGCAAAGGCAGGAUCGUGCUAUCUAAACAAGCAUCAUUCAGGAAUAGCCAAAACACAAAAAGAGGGAGAAGAUGCUUCUUUAUAUAGCAAACGGUACAACCAAAGUAUGGUUACAGCUGAACUUCAGCGGCUAGCUGAGAAGCAGGCAGCGAGACAGUAUUCUCCAUCCAGCCACAUCAACCUCCUCACCCAACAGGUAACAAACCUGAAUUUGGCAACUGGCAUCAUAAACAGAAGCAGUGCUUCAGCUCCCCCAACCCUCCGACCCAUCAUCAGUCCUAGUGGCCCGACAUGGUCUACACAGUCAGACCCCCAAGCUCCCGAGAAUCACUCCAGCUCUCCUGGAAGCAGGAGCCUGCAGACAGGGGGAUUUGCCUGGGAAGGAGAAGUAGAAAACAACGUGUACAGCCAGGCUACAGGGGUGGUCCCCCAGCACAAGUAUCACCCCACAGCAGGCAGCUAUCAGCUUCAAUUUGCCCUGCAGCAACUUGAACAACAAAAACUUCAGUCCCGGCAGCUCCUGGACCAGAGUCGAGCCCGGCACCAGGCAAUCUUUGGCAGCCAGACACUACCUAACUCCAAUUUAUGGACAAUGAAUAAUGGUGCAGGUUGUAGAAUUUCCAGUGCCACAGCUAGUGGCCAGAAGCCAACCACUCUGCCACAAAAAGUGGUACCACCUCCAAGUUCUUGCGCCUCCCUGGUUCCCAAACCCCCACCCAACCACGAACAAGUGCUCAGAAGGGCAACAUCCCAGAAAGCUUCCAAAGGGUCCUCCGCGGAAGGGCAGCUGAAUGGACUCCAGAGCAGCCUUAACCCUGCAGCCUUUGUGCCCAUCACCAGCUCUACAGAUCCUGCUCACACUAAAAUAUGAACCACAAACACACAGAGAAACAACCUGUUCACCACUCCUGGGUGCAUGAUUGAGGGUGAAGCAUCCACCAGCACUUCAAGGGGUCCAUAGUAUUUUUUUUUUUGCUGCCUCAAAGUCCCCAAAGCCUUCGAGCAGAAGUGGCAGUAGAUGGUUGCCAAUCAGCCAAUGCAGACUUUCACUGGGACAACAAGAAAGCAGAUCUUCUGGGUUUUGAUGGAACUUGGCAGUGGGGACAUUCAGCUGAUGCAUUAUAUACCCCGUCAGAGCACACUUGUAUCUUUUACCUUCCCUUUGCCCCAUGCCCCCAAACUGCUUAGGUCUUCUCUGUCCCUUUACUGCUGCUGCACAGAGAUGAUAUAAAAGAGGCUCUUUGGCUAUUUGCAUUUUGCUUCCUCUUCUUUUCCAGAUUACAGUAUGAAGCUUUAUUUUCUUUGUACAAGCUUAAAAUUUCAACAUCAUCAUCCGCCAAAGUUGUUCCUCCCUUUUCGGAGGAUCUAGGGGGAAAGAGGAGCAUUCAUCACAAGUUUCCUAGAGAGAGGAGACAAAUCGGUGUGCCAUUGACAACAUGAGCCAGGGUAAAGGCACCCUUUGGAAUUACUGAUUUCAAAGAUUAAUAAAGUAAUUCUAUUUUUA